GUAUGAUCUCGUGAAAUCUUGAGAGAAACUGAAUGACGAAUGAAACUAUUGUUCCUGUUUCACACAGAAGAAAACUGAGGUUGGCACUCAUCAUGAGCCCCUGUUCUCAUUCUGCAAAUGGUGAAGCUCUCUAUUGUCCUGACCCCACAGUUCCUGUCCCAUGACCAGGGCCAGCUCACCAAGGAGCUGCAGCAGCAUGUAAAGUCAGUGACAUGCCCAUGCGAGUACCUGAGGAAGGUUAUCAAUACUCUGGCUGACCAUCAUCAUCGUGGGACUGACUUUGGUGGAAGUCCUUGGUUACAUGUCAUUAUUGCGUUUCCGACAAGUUAUAAAGUUGUCAUUACCCUCUGGAUAGUUUACCUUUGGGUGUCUCUCCUGAAGACUAUCUUCUGGUCUCGAAAUGGACAUGAUGGAUCCACGGAUGUACAGCAGAGAGCCUGGAGGUCCAACCGCCGUAGACAGGAAGGGCUGAGGUCCAUUUGUAUGCACACAAAGAAAAGAGUUUCUUCCUUUCGAGGAAAUAAAAUUGGCCUGAAAGACGUCAUUACUCUACGGAGACAUGUGGAAACAAAAGUUAGAGCUAAAAUCCGUAAGAGGAAGGUGACAACGAAAAUCAACCAUCAUGACAAAAUCAAUGGAAAGAGGAAGACCGCCAGAAAACAGAAAAUGUUUCAACGUGCGCAAGAGUUGCGGCGGCGAGCAGAGGACUACCACAAAUGCAAAAUCCCCCCUUCUGCAAGAAAGGCUCUUUGCAACUGGGUCAGAAUGGCGGCAGCGGAGCAUCGUCAUUCUUCAGGAUUGCCCUACUGGCCCUACCUCACAGCUGAAACUUUAAAAAACAGGAUGGGCCACCAGCCACCUCCUCCAACUCAACAACAUUCUAUAACUGAUAACUCCCUGAGCCUCAAGACACCUCCCGAGUGUCUGCUCACUCCCCUUCCACCCUCAGCGGAUGAUAAUCUCAAGACACCUCCCGAGUGUGUGCUCACUCCCCUUCCACCCUCAGCGGAUGAUAAUCUCAAGACACCUCCCGAGUGUGUGCUCACUCCCCUUCCACCCUCAGCGGAUGAUAAUCUCAAGACACCUCCUGAGUGUCUGCUCACUCCCCUUCCACCCUCAGCGGAUGAUAAUCUCAAGACACCUCCCGAGUGUCUACUCACUCCCCUUCCACCCUCAGCUCUACCCUCAGCUCCACCCUCAGCGGAUGAUAAUCUCAAGACACGUGCCGAGUGUCUGCUCCAUCCCCUUCCACCCUCAGCGGAUGAUAAUCUCAAGACACCUUCCGAGCGUCAGCUCACUCCCCUUCCACCCUCAGCUCCACCCUCAGCAGAUGAUAAUAUCAAGACACCUGCCGAGCGUCUGCGGGGGCCGCUUCCACCCUCAGCGGAUGAUAAUCUCAAGACACCUUCCGAGCGUCAGCUCACUCCCCUUCCACCCUCAGCUCCACCCUCAGCAGAUGAUAAUAUCAAGACACCUGCCGAGCGUCUGCGGGGGCCGCUUCCACCCUCAGCGGAUGAUAAUCUCAAGACACCUUCCGAGCGUCCGACUCCCCUUCCACCCUCAGCUCCACCCUCAGCAGAUGAUAAUAUCAAGACACCUGCCGAGCGUCUGCGGGGGCCGCUUCCACCCUCAGCGGAUGAUAAUCUCAAGACACCUUCCGAGCGUCAUAUUGCCCUUCCACCCUCAGCAGAUGAUAAUAUCAAUACACCUGCCGAGCGUCUGCGGGGGCCGCUUCCACCCUCAGCGGAUGAUAAUCUCAAGACACCUUCCGAGCGUCAGCUCACUCCCCUUCCACCCUCAGCUCCACCCUCAGCAGAUGAUAAUAUCAAGACACCUGCCGAGCGUCUGCGGGGGCCGCUUCCACCCUCAGCGGAUGAUAAUCUCAAGACACCUUCCGAGCGUCAGCUCACUCCCCUUCCACCCUCAGCUCCACCCUCAGCAGAUGAUAAUAUCAAGACACCUGCCUUCCACCCUCAGCGGAUGAUCUCAAGACACCUUCCGAGCGUCAGCUCACUCCCCUUCCACCCUCAGCUCCACCCUCAGCAGAUGAUAAUAUCAAGAUACCUGCUGAGCGUCUGCGGAUUCCGCUUCCACCAUCAGCCGAUGAUAAUCUCAAGACACCUUCCGAGCGUCAGCUCACUCCCCUUCCACCCUCAGCUCCACCCUCAGCAGAUGAUAAUAUCAAGACACCUGCUGAGCGUCUGCGGGGGCCGCUUCCACCCUGAGCGGAUGAUAAUCUCAAGACACCUUCCGAGCGUCAGCUCACUCCCCUUCCACCCUCAGCUCCACCCUCAGCAGAUGAUAAUAUCAAGACACCUGCCGAGCGUCUGCGGGGGCCGCUUCCACCCUCAGCGGAUGAUAAUCUCAAGACACCUUCCGAGCGUCAGCUCACUCCCCUUCCACCCUCAGCUCCACCCUCAGCAGAUGAUAAUAUCAAGACACCUGCCGAGCGUCUGCGGGGGCCGCUUCCACCCUCAGCAGAUGAUAAUCUCAAGACACCUUCCGAGCGUCAGCUCACUCCCCUUCCACCCUCAGCUCCACCCUCAGCAGAUGAUAAUAUCAAGACACCUGCCGAGCGUCUGCGGGGGCCGCUUCCACCCUCAGCGGAUGAUAAUCUCAAGACACCUUCCGAGCGUCAGCUCACUCCCUUUCCACCCUCAGCUCCACCCUCAGCAGAUGAUAAUAUCAAGACACCUGCCGAGCGUCUGCGGGGAGCGUCUGCGGGGGCCGCUUCCACCCUCAGCGGAUGAUAAUCUCAAGACACCUUCCGAGCGUCAGCUCACUCCCCUUCCACCCUCAGCUCCACCCUCAGCAGAUGAUAAUAUCAAGACACCUGCCGAGCGUCUGCGGGGGCCGCUUCCACCCUCAGCGGAUGAUAAUCUCAAGACACCUUCCGAGCGUCAGCUCACUCCCCUUCCACCCUCAGCUCCACCCUCAGCAGAUGAUAAUAUCAAGACACCUGCUGAGCGUCUGCGGGGGCCGCUUCCACCCUCAGCGGAUGAUAAUCUCAAGACACCUUCCGAGCGUCAGCUCACUCCCCUUCCACCCUCAGCUCCACCCUCAGCAGAUGAUAAUAUCAAGACACCUGCCGAGCGUCUGCGGGGGCCGCUUCCACCCUCAGCCGAUGAUAAUCUCAAGACACCUCCCUUAGCUACUCAGGAGGCUGAGGCAGAAAAACCACGCAAACCCAAGAGGCAGAGGGCGGCUGAGAUGGAACCACCUCCCGAACCCAAGAGGCGGAGGGUCGGUGACGUGGAACCGUCACGCAAACCCAAGAGGCGGAGGGCCGCUGACGUGGAACCAUCAUCACCCGAACCCAAGAGGCGGAGGGUCGGUGAUGUGGAACCGUCACGCAAACCCAAGAGGCGGAGGGCCGCUGACGUGGAACCAUCAUCACCCGAACCCAAGAGGCGGAGGGUCGGUGACGUGGAACCGUCACGCAAACCCAAGAGGCGGAGGGCCGCUGACGUGGAACCAUCAUUACCCGAACCCAAGAGGCGGAGGUUGAGCUGAGAAGAGGCCAGUGCACUCAAGCCUGAGCAAUAAGAAUAAAACCGAGUAGAACAAAAUAAAAAAUUCAAAAAACAAAACAAAACCCACACUCCAAAAACUAACAAAGAAUAAAUAAAUAAUAUAAAAAUAAAAUAAAUACUGCAGUCCUUAUGUUA